GAUAAUAAUUCCAGCAUCGCAGGCUGUUCACCCAGCCUGUGAAUUUGUUAUUAAUAUCCUGAAAGGGAGAGGAUGAUAUUACUCCCCAUAAUAGACAGAUAUGACUCCCCAUAAUAGAGCACGAGGUGUACACCCACCCUGUGAUAUUCUUCCCAAUAUUCAAAGGCCGAGAGGUUGAUAUUACUCCAAAUAUCACCGCUCCGAUAGAUUGCAAAUGACCUGCUUUCUUUCUGAUCCCGGGCUGCUGAGUUCGGACCCCUGUUGGAUAGUAAAUCCCAAGUAAGGUACCUGCCUUCGGCAGCUCUGAGAUUUCUUCUUGGACACCUAAUACCCACAGUCCUCCAGGGGCAAGAGGAUGCUAUUACUGCAAAGAGUACAGAGGAUGUACACCCGUCUAUAAUAUAGUUGGUGAUUUCCAGAGGCUGAGAAGAUAUUACUGACAAUCCCGUCAACAUGCUGUGUGACCACCGUGGAUUGUAAUAUCCAGGAAAACGUUACUGCUAAUGUCACAGGACGUGUAGACCCUGCCAUCAAAUUCGUAAUAUCCUAGCGGGACUUCACUAGUCAUUUCACAAUGCGUGUGCACCCUUUGAUAUUAUUCGUAUUGUCCUGAAGAGAUGUUACUACUGAUGUCCCAAUGCAGAAAGCAGUUCCCUCCUUUGUGCAGUGCAGCUAGAAGAAAACAACAUUGUCUUGGGACACGCAUCAUUACUAAGAAUUUUUCCGUAAAUUUAUCUGUGUGCCUUCUACAGUUACCUGUGUGUCCCCUGUGGUACCUAUGGAAACCAGUUGUUGGGAAAUCCUUGUUAAGGUAUCUGAUGAAUCUCCAUAUCUCUUACACUGCACACAAUAAAUACCCAUUGAAUGAAUGAAUACAUAUAUGGAUGGAUGGACAGACGGAUGAUGCAUGGUAGAUGGAUGAAUACUGGAUCCCAUGCCCAUUGAGGGUUUGGGUCAGGGGACUGAUGUGAGCAGACACACAGAAGCACGGGCAGCCCCCGGCCUCCAGCAGAUUCUUCCAACCCAGCUGGAAAGACAUGAUAUGGACUUGGGAAUUCUCUAACUCUGAAAGGCCCCCUCUGCUGAGGUGUCCCAUGUUCACAGACAGUGUGCAUGACCAGAGAAAAUGGGCCUUGUAAUAGUACCUCUUAGGGCUGCUGUGAAGGAAGGAUAACAUGGAAGCAACAUGCCUAUCAUAGUGCUUUGUGUAUGCCCCUGUCAACCAUCACUCUACUUUGUGUGUGUGAGUUUGACCACCUGAAUCUUUUUGGCACCAUCUCAAGUAUAAUUCAAAUCACGAGGCAUUUGUGCAUAUCGACAAUACACCCAUCGUGGGAAAACUGGUUAUCGUGAAGCACAAAGGAGAUCAUGCCUACAAUGUCCCUUUGGGAGCCACGGGACACAAUGUGUGUGUUAGGGCGGGGUGGUCCAGCUGGACGACUGCCUGAAACAGCUGCAACACCAUGGGAACAGCAAUGUGGCUGGUGGCCCCUUCCGAGUGCCCCGUGCUGGGUGUCACACAAUGCCCCGUGACGUCCACAUUCCCUGCUGAGCCCGUCAAGAUCUGUACAGGAAACGACACCUCCUCCUUAGUGUGGUGGACCUCAGUUUUGAGGCCGAGAGUCCUCUGGCGCCCCCCACAGAGCUCCUGGAGAGACUGCCCAGCUAUGACUGGCUUCUUCAAGGGGGCAGAGGACAGAUAUUCUUCCCACCUUUGGAGGCCCCAGGGAGGCCCCAGGAGCAAAGGUCCUGGCCCUCGUUCCUGGAACACAGGAAGAACCCUGCUUCCUCCGGGGAGUCAUCUCUGGCCUCUCCAGCCCACAGUGUCUCUUGUGCUGCCAUCCAUGGAUCUGAAGACAGACGGGCCCCUCUGUGUGCCAGGGCUGGAGGAUGCUGGAGAUACAAGUGUGCAGAAUUGUGGAUUAAUGGCUCUCAGGGCUGCCAUGGAGAAAUGCAUGAAGAUGCAAGGGGAGGAAGGAGGAUUCUUUCCUCUUGGAGGUGUUGGGGCCAGAAAGACUUCAGAAAACCUGCCCCGUUCUCACGCUGGGCACCCGUUCACAUGGUCCCCUUUGCAGGAGAUGCCCUCCCCAGUUGGACUGCUGAGGGCUUUACCACUACCGUGGCCUCAGUUUCUCGCCUGCACGUUGAGGAGGCUGGCUGGCCCGCGUGAGUCCACAGGCCCUUCCCAGAAGCCCCCGCCUCUCUGUUCGGUCCCCUGCAGAGUCCCUGCGAUGACGGAGGAGGUGGCCCGGGAAGCCCUCCUCAGCUUUGUGGACUCUAAGUGCUGCUACAGCAGCACGGUGGCUGGAGACCUCGUCAUCCAGGAGCUGAAGCGGCAGACCCUCUGCAGGUACCGUCUGGAGACCUUUAGUGAAUCCAGGAUAAGCGAGUGGACAUUUCAACCCUUUACUAACCACUCUGUGGAUGGGCCGCAAAGAGGCGCCUCCCCCAGGCUCUGGGACAUCAAGGUUCAAGGUCCUCCGAUGUUUCAGGAAGACACCAGGAAGUUCCAGGUCCCUCACUCGUCACUGGUCAAGGAAUGCCACAAAUGCCAUGGGCGUGGGCGGUACAAGUGCAGCGGCUGCCACGGGGCGGGCACGGUGCGGUGCCCAUCCUGCUGCGGAGCCAAGCGCAAAGCCAAGCAGUCCCGGAGAUGUCAGCUGUGCGCGGGGUCCGGCAGGCGAAGAUGCAGCACUUGCUCAGGGAGAGGGAACAAGACCUGCGCCACCUGCAAGGGGGAGAAGAAGCUGUUGCACUUCAUCCAGCUUGUCAUCAUGUGGAAGAACAGCUUGUUUGAGUUUGUGUCUGAGCACCGGCUCAACUGCCCCAGGGAGCUCCUUGCUAAAGCCAAAGGAGAAAACCUCUUUAAGGAUGAAAACUCGGUGGUGUACCCCAUCGUGGACUUCCCUCUGCGAGACAUCUCUCUUGCCUCCCAGAGGGGCAUUGCAGAGCACAGCGCUGCCUUGGCCUCCCGUGCCCGCGUCCUGCAGCAGCGCCAGACCAUUGAGCUGAUCCCCCUCACAGAAGUUCACUAUUGGUACCAAGGAAAGACUUAUGUCUACUACAUCUAUGGCACUGACCACCAGGUGUAUGCGGUGGACUAUCCUGAGCGGUAUUGCUGUGGCUGUACCAUCGUGUGACAUAGCAUGGCUGUCCCCAGAGCCUGCCAUUCACGUUUGCCAAGGAAGAUGGCCGACACUCUCUGAGUGUGUUCACUGUUGGCUGCAUUGGACAAUCACAUACAAACCCUGGCAUGUCCUUCCAGAAAAACCAGCUUAUCAUCUAUCAAGCUCCAACCCCUUAUACAGCUCCUCUGGUGGAAUCCAUGACUCAUAUGUUUAACCUACAAUAAUUCAGCUAUACACAUUCCUGUAGAACAAAUGAGAGAAAUAAUUUAAAUGGCAAGGACUUUGCCUCUGGUCUCCAAGUUAAUGCCCCGAUGAUGCGUGUGAUUUGAUUUUGCUUUUUCCCUUUGUCGGUCUUGGUUCUGGUGUGCUUCUUCUAGUGGGAGCCUCUUGACGAUCUGAGUAUUACUGAAAUGUUCAAGGAUACACACAAAUAUCUGGCCCUAAUGCACAAUAAAUACUGCACUUAGGCAUAAAGUGCAAUAUGUUACUGCCCA